AGUGUUUUUCUAAGAUGGGUGGAGAAUAAGAGGUGCAGGUUGACUGUUCUUUAAGCCUCCUAGAGUGCCACAGUGGUUUCCAUUUCCUUACCUGCUUUGAGUCUGUGGAAGGAGACAGGAAUUCUGGAUCUGCAUCUCCAAUGGAUACUGAGGGGUUUGGUGAGCUCCUUCAGCAAGCUGAACAGCUUGCUGCUGAGACUGAGGGCAUCUCAGAGCUUCCCCAUGUGGAACGGAACUUACAGGAGAUCCAGCAGGCGGGAGAGCGCCUGCGUUCCCGUACCCUAACACGCACGUCCCAGGAGACGGCAGAUGUCAAGGCGUCAGUUCUCCUCGGGUCUCGGGGACUUGACAUAUCCCACAUCUCCCAGCGAUUGGAGAGUCUGAGUGCAGCCACCACCUUUGAGCCUCUUGAGCCUGUGAAGGACACUGACAUUCAGGGCUUCCUGAAGAAUGAGAAGGACAAUGCCCUGCUGUCUGCCAUCGAAGAGUCCCGGAAGAGGACCUUCGGCAUGGCUGAGGAGUACCAUCGGGAGUCAAUGUUGGUUGAGUGGGAGCAAGUGAAACAGCGAAUUCUGCACACACUGCUGGCAUCAGGAGAAGACGCCCUUGACUUUACUCAAGAAAGCGAGCCAAGCUACAUCAGUGAUGUGGGACCCCCUGGUCGAAGCUCUCUGGAUAACAUCGAGAUGGCCUAUGCGCGGCAAAUUUAUAUCUAUAAUGAGAAAAUUGUAAAUGGACACCUGCAGCCUAACCUGGUGGACCUUUGUGCUUCCGUCGCAGAGCUCGAUGAUAAGAGCAUUUCCGACAUGUGGACCAUGGUAAAACAAAUGACAGACGUGUUGUUGACACCGGCAACGGAUGCCCUGAAGAACCGCAGCAGCGUGGAAGUGCGCAUGGAGUUUGUCAGGCAGGCCUUGGCGUACCUUGAGCAGAGUUAUAAGAAUUACACCCUUGUGACUGUCUUUGGAAAUUUGCAUCAGGCCCAGCUGGGCGGGGUGCCUGGGACUUACCAAUUGGUUCGAAGUUUCCUGAACAUUAAACUGCCAGCUCCCUUGCCUGGACUACAGGAUGGAGAGGUGGAAGGCCAUCCUGUGUGGGCGCUAAUUUACUACUGCAUGCGCUGUGGAGACCUGCUUGCCGCUUCACAGGUAGUUAAUCGAGCCCAGCACCAGCUGGGAGAGUUUAAAACCUGGUUCCAGGAGUACAUGAACAGCAAGGACAGAAGAUUGUCCCCAGCUACGGAAAACAAGCUCCGGCUGCAUUACCGUAGGGCCCUCAGGAACAAUACAGAUCCCUACAAGCGGGCCGUGUACUGUAUCAUUGGCAGAUGUGACGUCACCGACAACCAGAGUGAAGUGGCGGACAAAACUGAGGAUUACCUGUGGCUGAAGUUGAACCAAGUGUGUUUUGACGACGAUGGCACCAGCUCCCCACAAGACAGGCUCACUCUCUCACAGUUCCAGAAGCAGUUGUUGGAAGACUAUGGCGAGUCCCACUUUACGGUGAACCAGCAACCCUUCCUCUACUUCCAAGUCCUGUUCCUGACAGCGCAGUUUGAAGCAGCAGUUGCCUUUCUUUUCCGCAUGGAGCGGCUGCGCUGCCAUGCUGUCCAUGUAGCACUGGUGCUGUUUGAGCUGAAGCUGCUUUUAAAGUCCUCUGGACAGAGUGCUCAGCUCCUCAGCCACGAGCCUGGUGACCCUCCUUGCUUGCGGCGGCUGAACUUCGUGCGGCUCCUCAUGCUGUACACCCGGAAGUUUGAGUCCACGGACCCAAGGGAGGCCCUCCAGUACUUCUAUUUCCUCAGGGAUGAGAAAGAUAGUCAAGGAGAAAACAUGUUUCUGCGCUGUGUGAGUGAGCUUGUGAUUGAAAGCCGAGAGUUCGAUAUGAUUCUUGGGAAACUAGAGAAUGACGGAAGUAGAAAGCCUGGAGUCAUAGAUAAGUUUACUAGUGACACAAAGCCUAUUAUCAACAAAGUUGCUUCUGUGGCAGAAAAUAAAGGACUGUUUGAAGAGGCAGCAAAGCUGUAUGACCUUGCCAAGAAUGCUGACAAGGUACUGGAGCUGAUGAACAAACUGCUGAGCCCUGUCGUCCCCCAGAUCAGUGCCCCGCAAUCCAACAAGGAGAGGCUGAAGAACAUGGCACUCUCCAUUGCCGAACGGUAUAGGGCUCAAGGAAUAAGCGCAAAUAAAUUUGUGGACUCCACGUUCUAUCUUCUUUUGGACUUGAUCACCUUUUUUGACGAGUAUCAUAGUGGUCAUAUUGAUAGAGCUUUUGAUAUCAUUGAGCGCUUGAAGCUGGUGCCCCUGAAUCAGGAAAGUGUGGAAGAGAGAGUGGCUGCCUUCAGAAAUUUCAGUGAUGAAAUCAGGCACAACCUCUCAGAAGUGCUUCUUGCCACCAUGAACAUCUUGUUCACACAGUUUAAGAGGCUCAAGGGGACAAGUCCAUCCUCGUCAUCCAGGCCCCAGCGAGUCAUCGAGGACCGCGACUCUCAACUCCGAAGUCAAGCCCGCACUCUGAUUACCUUUGCUGGAAUGAUACCAUACCGAACGUCUGGGGACACCAAUGCGAGGCUGGUGCAGAUGGAGGUCCUCAUGAAUUAAGUGCCAUGCUUUGUGGGAGUCUGGGUCGGCACACUGUCAGUACAUCAGGCACAUGGGCCCACUAGGCUGGGGUUUCUGGUUUUGUUUCUGUUGUGUUUUGUUUUGGUUUCUGUAUUAUGUAUUUUUGUCAACGCCAAUAAAUUUCUUUGAUUUGUAUUUCUUUUCAACAUUCUUUUAUUUUCUUUUUUUUUUUCUUUGAAAUUUUGUUUACAUUUUUAUUUGUGUAAUGGGAAAUACCGUCACUAGCUCUUGGGCCAGGGAAUGAGAGGCUAUGUAGAUAUUCAUUAUUUGGUUAAAUUGACCUUAAUUAAUUAAAAAUCUACCCAAAAUGAGCCAGGAAACAAAGCCUUUGGGAGUUACUUUUAUUUAGAUAUAAUAUUCCAUAUAGCAGAGUCACGAUUCAUUUUCACAUUUUUAUUUGAAUGUGAAAGUCAACCUCAGCCUUAGAAGAUGUAAGAUUUGUGUGUGAAAUAUCAAGCACUCCAUGUCCUCCUCUAGAGAGUGUGACUUAAGUCCAGAUGGUCCAAGACCAUCCCCCAAAUCAUCAGCUCUGAUUGCAGGAUUCAUCAGUUUGCCGUUCUGUUGCAAUCCCAGUGGAGAUAAAAGCAUAGACCUAGAAAAAGCCUUAAGAAGGAAGGUUGCAAGUGCCCCCAGCUUGCACUUGAGGAAGGGGUAAACCUUGCCACUGCACUCCUCUGUAGCUGCUCCACUGUGAGUUGACUGCUCGGCCUUGUACACACCCCUCCUAGAAAGACGUUUAAGCCCCUAUUUCCCUUCUCUGGUGGUCAGUUCCUCUGCUCAGACGACCCCCUUCCCCACUCAUUAAGGUAAUUGGCCAGGCAGGCUCAUGGGUCACGUGCUGAGUCUGCAAUGUACAGAAUCCAGACCACCACAUGGCAUCAGCACCAUGGGUGUUUGCUCCCUGAGCAGUAGUUGUCACCCAUCAUUUGCUCUGUUUCCCCCACCAUCAGUCCCAAAGCCCUAGACUAAACCAGAGAGCAAAUUAGGUCGUGUUUGUUCCUGAAUGGGCCAACUGGAGCCUUGAGACAGUGGGCAGUGGUCUGCUCUGCUGGUUUGAUGGACGGCUCCCUGAGGUAGACUCUUUCCCAGCAGAAUGUUAAGAUCCCCAAAGGGUCCCCAAAGGUGCCUUUGCUUGUAGGGAGAAGUUUCUGUCUUGUCACAGGGUGUGGUCAUCCCCACUGUCUCCCAGUUGUUAAAAUAAUUGUUACCUUUUCUUUUGGGAAGAAAUAAUCUGUAGAUAAUGGAACCAACUGCUGCUUAUCGGUAGGAUUCCAUGUUCCAGGAAGGAUGCGGCCUGAGGGUCAGUGGAGCUGUGUUCUGCCUUCCUCCUCUAGUCCCAUCUUGUCACCCUGGAGGACUGUCUUCAAUUGAGCUUUACUAGAAAGUCUUGAAACAUGAGCCCUGCAGAGGCCUUGAUUUAGCAAGUUGUGCCCUGCUUAUAUGUGCUGAUUUAAGCUAAUCAAAUGAUUUAAUAGUGCUUUUUAAAAAAGAGUACUCCUGGCCGGGUGGGGUGGCUCACACCUGUAAUCCUAGCACUUUGGGAGGCCAAGGCAGGUGAUCACCUGAGAUCAGGAGUUCAAGACCAGCCUGGCCAACAUUGUGACACCCCGUCUAUACUAAAAAUACAAAAAUUAGCCGGGCAUGGUGGCAGGCACCUGUAAUCCCAGCUACACAGGAAGCUGAGACAGAAUUGCUUGAACCCGGGAGGCGAAGGUUGCAGUGAUCUGAGAUCAUGCCACUGCACUCCAGCCUGGGUGAAAGAGCGAUACUCCGUCUCAAAAAAAUAAAGAGUACUCUGGCCGAGUGCAGUGGCUCACGCCUGUAACCCCAGCACUUUGGGAGGCCAAGGCAGGCAGUUCGCUUGAGGUAAGGGGUUUGAGACCAGUCUGGCCAACAUGGGGAAACCCCGUUUCUACUAAAAAUACAAAAAUCAGCUGGGCAUGGUGGCAGGCGCCUGUAAUCCCAGCUACUCGGGAGGCUGAGGCAGGAGAAUCACUUGAACCCAAGAGGCGGAGGUUGCAGUGAGCCGAGCUUAUGCCACUGCACUCCAGCCUAGGCGAUGGAGUGAGGCUCUGAUUCAAAAAUAAAAAUAAGAGUACUCUGUGGACUUUUCAUAAAGUGCAACUUAGUGCUUUGUUUUUCUAAUACUAGAUUUUACUUGCAGAUAGAAAUAUAACAAUGCCACAAAUGAGAAGGCUCAAGUUGUUUAAAUACAUGUUUGCUCCUGGCUUACCUCUUCUUCACUAUCCCAUGAGAAUCGUGGAUUUGCCUUUCCUUGCAUCCUGCAGUUCUACUUGUCUCAGAGAGAACUGCACACCAGCCCUGCAUCCAGGGGAUGAGGUUCUUUGACCUGUAGAUGGGUCCUAAAAUGAGAAGGGAGAGAAGCAGCCAGACCUUGAGCUGCUCUGCUAGGGGAGCUGUGAGUUGGGAGAAAAGUGGUCACUGGUUGGCAGUUAAGGACUUGCUGAGAGAGACAUUUGUAGGAGAAAGAAGAUAAGUAGGUUCAUACCAGAAGGGCCAGGACUCGGAUGGAGCAAAUCCCAGUUCUUGUCCUACAAGCUGAUUGUGCGAUUGAGCACAGGCCUCUGGAAUUGUGCAGAGAUGAGAAACAGGCUGAAUUUGCAAGGCCACAACAUCAGGUUGUCAUGUACCCAUCAUUACAGCUUAUGCCCAGAAGUCCUGACCCUGUGACAGGUUAUUAUCUUAAAAACUCAUCUUCAGCCCACUUUUUCAGAGAACUAACUCUUUCCUUAGAUGUUGGGCCAGGAUUUCACUAUUUACCCAGAGAAACUAAGAGAAAGUGGCACUAGGCGUCUUGUCUUCCAGAUGUGAGAUUUCGAUCUUUCUAAUGAAAUUGGGGGCACUUUGAGACUGUCAGGGUUUGUUCCUGUCUCAGAAUGGCUCAUAAUAAACUCACUGAAACACUCAAAGGAAAGUACUGACUUGAUCUGGAUCCUUUUCAGAGGCCUGGAGAUUUAAUUUCACAGAUUCUCUUCUUUUGGCUCAACAACAACAGCAACAAAAAACUCUUUGACUCCCCAACUUCAGAGGGAAAACUGAAGCGAAACUGGUGAGCUCUGCCACGGCAGAUGCCUUCCUUUUUCACUCACGAGCUGGGCGGGCUCAUCAAAGAGCAGGAAGUGCCCAUUUUACACUGGGGCCAGGAUGCAGACCCAGCUCCUGUCCUCCGCGAACUUACAGUCUAAUUAGAGCCUCUUAAGGACAAUUUGGCAGCCACUGUUAACUCUUGAUGCAUCAUUUAAAUCCUAGAACAGGCAGCUUUAAAGCAAAGAACUACAGACUUUUCCGCAGUGUCCAGCAUUUGCUGACCAAAAAAAACCUGAGGGUGAUUUUUCUCUCUUUGAAUUUUUACCCUUGCCUGCACCUAGCCAGAACCCUUAAUACUAAAUUUGCAGUUAUAUGCAGCUCUGCCAACGCCUUCCUGCUUUAGACUGGAUCUCUACUAUCCUUUUUCUCUACUAGGCACCAGAACCUUUGUCUAGUUCAUUAGGUGGUUCACAUCACUUGCCAAAUUUCCAGCAUGCCACUCAGGAAGUGACUUGAGCAUGCUGAAUGCUGAGUCAGAAAAUGAACCCCUGGGCUGGCGGGUUGACCCAGGCCUGACAAAGUCUUGGCAGUCCCCACACUGACUGCGAACUCUCCCUUAGCCUCAGUCAGCUGGGAAAGGAAUUGAGCCCUGUGUCAGCAAAUUGGGAGAAAGUGUUACAUAUAAAAUUCUUGAUGGAAAUGUGUGUUUUAUAUCAGAAUUGAGCUUUUGUUCCUGCAUCUCAGAAAUACCAGGAAGAAGUCAGCAUCUCAUUAAACAGGAGUUGUCUAAACUGUGGAAGAAAAUAUCCCCCAUUCUUUAUCCUACGCUGAAUCCACAAGUCUUCCCAUCUUCCACCAUCUUCUGACAGUUCCAUAAUAUAUUGGUAUCCCUCACAGGGCAGGGACAGGAAGGAAAUAAAUCUUUCUGCCACUUGUUUCCAACCGAAAAGGAAAAAAGUUAAAAAUUACUAAAGUGUUCUGAAAAGAGAUUUCAAGUGGUCUGUGCUGCUUUUUUGCCUUGUUACGCACAUAACUUGUGACUGGCUAGAUAGGCCACGUGUAUUUAUCAGCCAAGAUUCCAUUGCAGCAGAUGAUUUCAAAACCUCUUUGUGUGCUGGGCCGUGCUAGGUAGCUGGAAUAUCUGAGGUAAAUUAAGCACUGAUUUGUUCCCAGAGUUGUGCAUAAUUCUUUAAAAGUAGGCUCGUUUUUUUCGUUUUUUUGUCCAGGAUCACCUAAGUGAAGUACUCGUGGUUCUAAGUUGCUAACCCAGGGAAAGAGGAUAUUUUCCUGUCCUAACCUUGGUUUUUGAAAUAUGCUUCUCCUGUGUGCCCUCUCUGGGGUAUCUGGCCCACAGUAGAUUGCUCAGCAGAUAUUUGAAUGAGCAGAUGCUUUGCUUUGUCCUCCUGUGCCAGGCUCCUCCCCACAUCCUCUGGAUCAGCUCCACGUGCCUAGAUUCAGACUCCGUGAUUCACCGUGGGGGCCCUUAAUAGGCAUUCAGUCUGAAAGAAGGUGGAGGAGAAUAAUGUCUCCCAGGAUCAAAUGAGACUCAGGGCUGUUCCUUCAAAGACAGAAACUUGCAGAGCUGCACAGCAGCAGGGAAACAUUGAGAAGGGGGUGGAAAUUUGAUGUACUGUGAAUAAUGAAGGCCGGAUCUUUAAAAAGAAAAAGGGACGGGGUGCUGGCAGAAACCCAGCUCUGCGCUAGCACAAUCUGUACACCUGGCUGCCUUUGCCCUUGAGCUUCUAUUUCUUGGGGAUGGGGAGGGCAAAAAAGUUUGCCCCAGACACUGGCUUCUGUUUGAACAGGAAGUGGGGAGUCAGUGAUCCCAGAGGGGACUUCAGCAUCAGGACAUAUGCUUUGGUGGCCUCAGCAGACCUGGCCUAGGCAGGCUUUCAGGUGGCACCCAGGGGCUUUAUGGCCUGCAGGUAAGGCCCCUUCAUCCGGGUCAGACUUAGCAAAUAAAAAUAUAGGACACUCAAUUAAGUUUGCAUUUUGGAUAAACAGUGAAGAAGUUCCUAGUGUAAGUAUGUCCCAGUUCUAUGUGGCUGCCCUACCUGGGCUUGCCUCUGCUGGUACUAGCUGCCCAGAGACCUUCAGGCCUGCCACGGGCUGCCGGGAGCUCUCUAGUGGAAUUGGAUUACCCUGAUUUUGUGCAUUGUUUGUGCUUUUGUGGGCAUCGGAAAUGACUGAGAUACGCAGUUUUGAAGAGCUAGGCAGGCAGCUGAGCGGGAUAAUGUGGGCCCCAGUUGACCUCAGUGGCUGUCAUCUACUGUGUUUUUCAACCAGGAAUUUCAAAUACUGUGUAUUUUAGAAAGAAAGGAAAGAGCCAAAGUACAGCCUUUUCUCACUUGAUCAGUAACUUGUGUUAGAAACUCAGUGGGGGAGAAUUCUUUGCGUUUUUCAGUUGACUGAUUAUUUUCCUUUUUUUCUUUUUUGCUUUUCUCGAGUCACUCUGUGUGGUGCUUGUGGGAGAAGGGAGAGGGUGGGAGAGCGUUGGUGGAUGUGUUCUGCAUGUUCCUUUCUGUACAGUAACUUCUGCAUUUACUCUGUUUAGGAUGGUUCCUUCACCACUAUCCCUGUCUGUAGCCAGUAAAUUUCUGGAAUAUUC